ACACUCCCGGCUUCUUCUGGCUCAGCCGCUCGGCUCCCCGGGGAGGCCUGGGCUGUGCUGGUGGGGAUGGGGUCCGGGCGAGGCCGUGUUUGUAGGGGAACGUCAGACGGAGAGACCUCCGAAGAUUUCGUGCUCGUUUCCCCCGGCCCUCAGGCUCCGGGCACUGAAAGGCAGUCACCCACCGCAGCCCUUCCAGCCCUGUCUACAGCGCCUCGGGCCUGGGGGCAGUGAGUGAGGGGUGGGUGUUGCUGAAACCAUCCGUAACGGCUCCAACGUUCGCUGAGGAGAGCCCGGCCAACUCCUUCCUCCGUGGCCGGAACUGGGAUUGGCAGCCACCAUUUGCAUGUGAUGUUGAUAAACUUCAUUUUACGCCACGUAUCCAGAGACUGAAUGAAUUGGAGGCCCAAACUCGUGUAAAAUUGAAUUUCUUGGACCAGAUUGCAAAGUACUGGGAGUUACAGGGAAGUACUCUGAAAAUUCCACAUGUGGAGAGGAAGAUCUUGGACUUAUUUCAGCUUAAUAAGUUAGUUGCAGAAGAAGGUGGAUUUGCAGUUGUUUGCAAGGAUAGAAAAUGGACCAAAAUUGCUACCAAGAUGGGGUUUGCUCCUGGCAAAGCAGUGGGCUCACAUAUCAGAGGGCAUUAUGAACGAAUUCUCAACCCCUACAACUUAUUCCUGUCCGGAGACAGCCUAAGGUGUUUGCAGAAGCCAAACCUGACCACAGACACUAAGGACAAGGAGUACAAACCCCAUGAUAUUCCCCAGAGGCAGUCUGUGCAGCCUUCGGAAACGUGCCCCCCAGCCCGACGAGCAAAACGCAUGAGAGCAGAGAGACAGAGUCUCGCUGUGUUGCCCAGGCUGGAGUGCAGUGGCGCGAUCUUGGCUCACUGCAACCUCCGCCUCCUAGAUUCCAGCAAUUCUUCUGCCUCAGCCUCCCAAGCCAUGAAUAUUAAAAUAGAACCCGAGGAGACAACGGAAGCCAGAACUCAUAAUCUGAGACGUCGAAUGGGUUGUCCAACUCCAAAAUGUGAAAAUGAGAAAGAAAUGAAGAGUAGCAUCAAGCAAGAACCUAUUGAGAGGAAAGAUUAUAUUGUAGAAAAUGAGAAGGAAAAGCCCAAGAGUCGAUCUAAAAAAGCCACCAAUGCUGUGGACCUGUAUGUCUGUCUUUUAUGUGGCAGUGGCAAUGAUGAAGACCGGCUACUGUUGUGUGAUGGCUGUGAUGACAGUUACCAUACCUUUUGCUUGAUCCCACCUCUCCAUGAUGUUCCCAAGGGAGACUGGAGGUGUCCUAAGUGUUUGGCUCAGGAAUGUAGUAAGCCACAAGAAGCAUUUGGCUUUGAACAAGCAGCCAGGGACUAUACCCUCCGUACUUUUGGGGAAAUGGCAGAUGCGUUCAAAUCUGAUUACUUCAACAUGCCAGUCCAUAUGGUCCCCACAGAGCUUGUUGAGAAAGAAUUUUGGAGACUAGUAAGCACUAUUGAGGAGGAUGUCACAGUGGAAUAUGGAGCUGACAUUGCCUCAAAGGAAUUUGGCAGUGGCUUUCCUGUCCGAGAUGGGAAAAUCAAACUCUCACCUGAGGAAGAGGAGUAUCUUGAUAGUGGCUGGAAUUUGAACAACAUGCCAGUGAUGGAGCAGUCUGUCCUUGCACAUAUUACUGCUGAUAUAUGUGGCAUGAAACUUCCUUGGUUGUAUGUGGGAAUGUGCUUUUCUUCAUUCUGUUGGCACAUUGAAGACCACUGGAGCUAUUCAAUUAACUACUUGCACUGGGGUGAGCCAAAAACCUGGUAUGGAGUCCCAGGGUAUGCUGCUGAGCAGCUAGAAAAUGUAAUGAAGAAACUAGCUCCAGAACUCUUUGUGUCCCAGCCGGAUCUCCUCCAUCAGCUUGUGACCAUCAUGAACCCCAAUACCCUGAUGACUCAUGAAGUGCCUGUUUACCGAACUAAUCAGUGUGCUGGGGAGUUUGUGAUUACAUUUCCAAGAGCCUACCACAGUGGUUUUAACCAGGGUUUUAAUUUUGCUGAGGCUGUUAACUUCUGCACUGUUGAUUGGCUGCCAUUAGGCCGACAGUGUGUGGAGCAUUAUCGCUUGCUUCAUCGAUAUUGUGUGUUUUCCCACGAUGAGAUGAUCUGCAAGAUGGCUUCCAAGGCUGAUGUAUUAGAUGUUGUAGUGGCUUCAACUGUUCAGAAAGACAUGGCCAUUAUGAUUGAGGAUGAGAAAGCUUUAAGAGAAACUGUCCGUAAAUUGGGAGUGAUUGAUUCGGAAAGAAUGGAUUUUGAGCUGUUGCCAGAUGAUGAACGUCAGUGUGUAAAAUGCAAAACUACAUGCUUCAUGUCUGCCAUCUCCUGUUCUUGUAAACCUGGCCUUCUUGUUUGCCUGCAUCAUGUAAAAGAAUUGUGUUCCUGUCCUCCUUACAAAUAUAAAUUGCGGUAUAGGUACACGCUGGAUGAUCUCUACCCUAUGAUGAAUGCAUUGAAGCUUCGAGCAGAAUCUUACAACGAAUGGGCCUUGAAUGUGAAUGAAGCUUUGGAGGCAAAGAUCAACAAGAAGAAAAGCCUUGUCAGCUUCAAGGCUUUAAUUGAAGAAUCUGAAAUGAAGAAAUUCCCAGACAAUGAUCUUUUGCGACACCUUCGCCUAGUCACACAGGAUGCAGAGAAGUGUGCCUCUGUUGCGCAGCAGUUGCUUAAUGGCAAAAGGCAAACUAGAUAUCGAUCUGGUGGAGGGAAAUCCCAAAAUCAGUUGACAGUGAAUGAGCUCCGGCAGUUUGUAACACAGCUGUAUGCUCUUCCAUGUGUCCUCAGUCAGACACCAUUACUAAAGGAUCUCUUGAAUCGUGUAGAAGAUUUUCAACAGCAUAGUCAGAAACUACUCUCUGAGGAAACGCCUAGUGCUGCGGAGCUGCAGGACUUGCUAGAUGUCAGCUUUGAAUUUGAUGUUGAACUUCCACAGCUUGCUGAGAUGCGUAUCCGUUUGGAACAAGCCCGUUGGCUAGAAGAGGUGCAGCAAGCUUGCCUAGACCCCAGCUCCCUUACUUUAGAUGAUAUGAGACGUCUCAUAGACCUAGGGGUAGGGCUGGCCCCGUAUUCAGCAGUGGAGAAAGCUAUGGCCCGGCUGCAGGAACUGCUCACAGUGUCAGAGCACUGGGACGACAAAGCCAAGAGUCUCCUCAAGGCCAGGCCACGACAUUCAUUGAAUAGCCUUGCUACGGCAGUAAAGGAAAUCGAAGAGAUCCCUGCAUAUCUGCCCAAUGGUGCGGCUCUGAAAGACUCAGUGCAGAGAGCCAGAGACUGGCUUCAGGAUGUAGAGGGCCUGCAGGCUGGAGGACGUGUGCCAGUGUUAGACACACUCAUAGAACUUGUUACACGAGGCCGAUCUAUCCCCGUACAUCUGAAUUCUUUGCCAAGACUGGAAACCCUAGUAGCUGAGGUUCAGGCUUGGAAAGAAUGUGCUGUUAAUACAUUCUUGACUGAGAAUUCUCCAUAUUCUCUCUUAGAGGUGCUGUGUCCUCGAUGUGAUAUUGGCCUUUUGGGAUUGAAAAGGAAGCAGAGAAAGUUAAAGGAGCCCUUGCCAAAUGGAAAGAAAAAAAGCACCAAAUUAGAGAGUCUGAGUGACCUGGAGAGAGCUUUAACUGAAAGCAAGGAGACUGCUUCAGCUAUGGCAACUCUUGGGGAAGCUCGCCUAAGGGAAAUGGAAGCCUUGCAGUCUCUCAGACUCGCCAAUGAAGGGAAAUUGCUGUCGCCUCUCCAAGAUGUGGAUAUAAAAAUCUGCCUAUGUCAGAAGGCCCCAGCUGCCCCUAUGAUUCAAUGUGAACUCUGCAGGGAUGCUUUCCACACCAGUUGUGUGGCGGUACCCAGUAUUUCACAGGGCCUGCGAAUCUGGCUUUGUCCCCAUUGUCGGAGGUCAGAGAAACCUCCAUUAGAGAAAAUUCUGCCCCUGCUCGCCUCCCUUCAGCGUAUCCGAGUUCGCCUUCCUGAGGGAGAUGCACUUCGAUAUAUGAUUGAAAGAACCGUGAACUGGCAGCACAGAGCCCAGCAACUGCUUUCGUCAGGGAAUCUUAAAUUUGUGCAAGAUCGAGUGGGCUCAGGACUGUUAUAUAGCAGAUGGCAAGCCUCAGCAGGACAGGUGUCAGACACAAACAAGGUAUCUCAACCUCCUGGCACAACAUCAUUUUCUUUGCCUGAUGACUGGGACAACAGAACCUCAUAUUUGCACUCCCCCUUCUCAACUGGACGAAGUUGUAUCCCCCUCCAUGGUGUUAGUCCAGAAGUGAAUGAACUAUUGAUGGAAGCCCAGCUGCUCCAGGUAUCCCUUCCUGAAAUUCAGGAACUUUACCAGACUUUACUUGCAAAGCCAAGCCCUGCUCAGCAGACUGACCGAAGCUCACCAGUGAGACCCAGCAGUGAGAAGAAUGACUGUUGCCGAGGGAAGCGAGAUGGAAUUAACAGUCUUGAGAGAAAACUGAAGAGACGCCUGGAAAGAGAGGGCCUCUCCAGUGAGCGGUGGGAACGAGUUAAGAAAAUGCGGACCCCCAAAAAGAAGAAAAUCAAACUGAGCCACCCCAAGGACAUGAACAAUUUCAAGUUAGAGAGAGAGCGUAGCUAUGAAUUAGUUCGUUCUGCUGAAACUCAUUCCCUGCCCUCAGACACAUCCUAUUCCGAACAGGAAGACUCUGAGGAUGAAGAUGCCAUCUGCCCAGCUGUGAGCUGCCUGCAGCCAGAAGGAGAUGAGGUGGACUGGGUCCAGUGUGAUGGCAGCUGCAAUCAGUGGUUUCAUCAGGUCUGUGUUGGUGUCUCCCCAGAGAUGGCAGAGAAAGAAGACUACAUCUGUGUGCGCUGUACUGUGAAGGACGCACCAAGCCGAAAGUAAAAACACAAAAACAGAUACCCCCCUACUUAAUGUAAUUCAGGACUCCAACCAAGAGGAUUUCUUCAAAUCUCAGCAAAGCUACAGGACUGGUACUCAAGCCAGCCUGUAAACGGUGCUAUUUCUAUUCCUUAUGGGAUCAUUUUUCCAGGACUCUUUGAAGAAAAGAAAAAACAACUAAAAAAAUUUUUGACACUUUUUGUAUUUUUUCCUUAAGAGCUAUUUGUGGUUGUUGAGGUUUGAAAAGCUGACUGUUUUUUUUGCAGGGGUUCCCACCAAUUUGGAAGGCAUUGAAGCUUGCACCUUUUCAUGUACAGCAUUAAAAUUUUACCUCUCUCUGGGAUUUACCAGCUUAAGAGUCCAACUCACUUCCAGUGCCCAAAAGGGCACCCACCAGAAAUUCCAGUAAAUCCUCAUUUGAGGAAGCUCUCCCUUGUUUACUCUGUUACCACAUUGGGGAAAUUUUUAAGUUUUUCACUUUGGGAGUUUUUGUUUGUUUCUUCUUUUCCUUUAUCCACUUUUCUUCUUCCUGGUAGACUAGGUUUAUUUAUCUGAGCAAUAACUUCUAUGUUGGUUUCAGUGGCUGGAAUUAAAACAAAACAAAACAAACUUCCAAACAGUGUGUUGGUGCUUUAGCGAUUGAUUGAUGUACAGAACACAAAUGUCUAGUUUCUAGUGUCACUGAUGAACUAGUGAUGUAGAAAAGAGACUUCUCUGUAAGUAAUUGCCACAGCUGUAUUUUGGCUUUCUCCCUGUCCCUUCCUUUCUCCCCUAUUUUUUGGUAGCUUGUAUCAAAUGUUACAGUUUAUAUUGUGGAAUAAAUCCUUCGUCCUAACAUAACACUAAAUGCUGAUUAUUUAGAGCCAUUAGAGCACAGCUUCUUCUGCCCCUCUACUGUUGCACAGCCAGAAGGGGCUGCUUGCUUUUGCCUCUGCCCAACCAGGUUGCAGUAGCAGUGGAUGUUAGCCUGCAAACAACAUUAGGGGAUUCUUCUUUUGUGUCCUGCUCUGUUUGGUGGGCCAUAUGCCUACAGCCCUCACUAACAAAGAACCCCUCUGUCUUCAAGGACUAGAACCUAUCUUUAAAGCCGUGCUCUUUUAAAAUAAGCUUUCUCAGAAUGUUGGCAAAUCACUUCAAUCCUCAAAUCAGUCUUCCUUGUGGAAUGCUGCCUUUAUUAUAUUUGAAUUGACAGGGGAACUUGGUUUAGGGUUAAGACGUUGGAAGGAAAUCUAAGGAAAAUUAAUCCUCACAGAGGUCCGGGUUUAGUAUAUGUCUUGAGAGGAGACUUGUGAAUUCCCAGACUCUGCCUCCUGGUUUCCUUUCUCAUUUCUUUCUAACUGUAGCUAUCAUUACUGGCUGUGGAUAGCCCAUAGCUAUUUUCCUUGCUUUUCUUUUUUAAAGGGGUCUGUUCUGCAGUGGAGAAGACAUUCUGGUGACCAGACUUUUGCUUACCUUUUCCUAUUCUGUUGCCAAUUUUUGUUUUCCCCACAUUCUAUAGCCAUAAACCUGAAGAUGAGUAAAACUGGUGGGUCUUUAAUAAAACAACAACAAAAACAGCAGUUUGUGAUAUAGCAGAGGUUUAAAUGUACCCUCCCCUUUUAUGCACUUCAAAUAAUUAAAUCUCUUUAAGAAUGACUUCUAGUUGUCUGCAGUUUUCUGCAGUUGUUGUGAUGUUUCUCUUCGUCUGAUGGUGGUUCUGGGGCCAAUAGAGAAGAAUAGUCUCCAGAGUACAAUUUGGAAUCAUCGUGGUUUGGCCUUGUUAGUAUUCAAAUUCUUAGAAUCCCCUCCAUCACCCCCGACUUUGAGAUAGGAUGCCAACUGUCCCAGUCCUCACCUUCCAUUGAGAAAUUAAGCUUAAAAGGAGACCCUGCUGCUAAUAUAAAGCCACUGCCUUUAGAGAGCUUUUGCCAUCUUAGUAAGCACAACCCCUACCCCCAUCCCCACUAGUUUUUCUUCUUCACCUGUGGGUGGUGGUACACAGUCCCUGACAAUAGCAUCUUUGAGGAAGUCAGAUCUUUGUAUCUCUGAGUGAGUUAGAAAAGGUAGGCAUGUGUGUAUUUGAACCACUCCCUCCCUGGAUGAGAACCACUGAUCAUUUUAUGUGUGAUGAUGCUGAAUUUAAAGAGAAUGUCAGUUGCCCAAAGCUACACUGUACUACUAGUAAAUAACAAAGCCUGGGUUUUAUCUUCCAGUUUUCCUACAGUAUUCCUCCUACCUUGUACACCAUCACACUACUAAUGAACACAGAUAACGUUUACUUUCCAGUUUAUGCCUUUGUUGUAUCCCUAAAAUGACUACAGACUGAUGUGAUCUAAAAACCAUGUUUCAUUGUGUGUUAGCUGUGAAGCUGGCCUGUACCAGAGAAACCUCUGAACUUGUAGGGGAAAAUGAUAAAAUGCACAUGGAAACUGACACUUCAGUUUCCAUCUCAGUAGUCCUGCAGCUUUGUGAGGUGGGAGAGGGGAAGGGACUGUGUUAAGUUAGAGCCUGAACCAGAAGGAGGGUCAGUGGGUAAAGAAAGAAAGGGUAGAUGAGGUGUGCCUUCCACCUCACCUAAAUGAAUACUGUUUGUUUUUUGUUUUUCCUUCCAGAUUAGACUUUGGGGGAUUUCUUAUAUAGAAUAAAGGGCUUGAUUAUAUGUAGCCUCUAUCCUGGAGAAAGGUUAUGUAAUUUGGACUAUGUAAAGGAAGUUGACUUCUUUACAGCUUCGUUUCAGUAUCCUAGGAGGUGGGAUUCAUUUUUCUAUCUUAAGUUAACCUAAAGGAGAGAUGCCACUUGUGGUGAUGGAGGUUGUUAAAAACCUGAAUUUCCCUGCUUCAUUCUCCAGUGAAGAGCUUAAGAAAAUGAGGCUUUGGAUAUUUUGGCAGAAGUGUCUGAAAUGCACCUGAUUUGCCAUUAUACCCACCAUCAAAAGCAACAUGGCCCUUUGGGUAUUAGUGCAAGAUUAGCCUAAGAAUAGAGUAGAUCUCUACCUGGAAGAGGGUGAAACAUGGCUCUCUACUGAUUUGGGUUGUACUCUGAAGGCCCUUUGUAAUGGGUUUCUGCCUCUUUGUAUUUCACUUAAAAAAUCUUGAUGGAUAUUUGGCAGUCUGUUAAGACCUGCUUCUGGCUUGGAGCAGGUAUUGAUUGGUAUUUAGUACCCAUGGGUGUUUUUCUGGGCUCAGUCUUGCCUAUGUUUCUUGCCAUAUGACACAUACCGGAAUGGAUUCCAGAUGCUAUAUACCUGUAACAGGAGACAGAAUUGGACAACAAGGAUUUUAAGAGUCAUUGCCCAUUGUAAAGCAUUAAGCCAGAGCUGGUUAUUCAUUAUCAGACUAACUACAUACUAGUCCAUGCUAGUGUCAGCCUAUAUUAAAAUAGUCUUUCCUUGCCAUAGUGCUGGCGAAAACCCAAUCCCUUCUGAUGAAACAUUGCUUCUUGGGAAGACAAGCUGAGGAAAGCAAUGAAGAUCCCAGUGUCGGCCUUUAUUGAGCUAUGUAUGAGGGUCAGGGUCCCUCAACUCCUAGUGACUAUGAAGCAGCAGUGUGAUGGCUUCGCCCUCUUUGCCCCUCUGUCAUCAAUCCUUUGCAUGUGGCUAUUUUAAGCUUCUCAGCUUUCUUUUGGGAGGCUUCAUGUGUAACUUAUUAUAGAAAUGUUACUGAAAAGCUGCCUAAACAAAAAAUUGUAUAAAGUAGGAAUUUGUAUAAAGUAAUACUGUUGUAAAUCCAUCUUCAAGAUGUAAAGAAUCAAUUUGUAAAGUGUAUAUUUUCACUUCUCCCUUCAAAUUUAUGUGAACAAGUUUUUCAUGUUUCAAUAUUGCUUACAUAGGAAUACACCUUACGUUUUUAUCAGUAUAAAUGGAACAUUUAAAACCAGUCAACAACAGAACAGAUAAUCCAGCUCCCUGUUUGUGUUCUGGGUUAAUUUUGCAAGGAUGAAGGGCUAGAAAGUGGUGAGUUUCGGUGUGUUUCUUAUUUUCAGGAUAACCGGCUGCAUUGCAGUAGAGGAAUGGAAUGGUGAGGUCAUUUGACCUGUUCCAGGUGAGUGGAGGCCAAAGAACAUUCUUUCUGCCUCCCCUUGGAUGGGAAAAUUGAGAAAUUAAAAAGUUGCCUUUCUGAGGAAACAAAAGUUAUUUUCUCUAUUUAAAAUAAAUGUCCAAAGGCACCCCUCUAAACACCAAAACUUUUAGCUCCUGGCAAACUUACCUAGCUAGAAGUUGGAGAAGAGUGCGGUUUCAAACCAUGCUUCCUUUCUGCCCUUGCCAAUACGUUCUCACUGACUGUGAUUCUGCUGUGAACACACACACACACACAAACACACACACAAGCCCCUUCUGUGUAUGAUCAGGACAAGUAGUUCAACAGUUAAUAAAAAAGUUAAAUUAUUGGAUGAGAAAGAUAUAUUUAACCUAAAUCAUAAAUAUGUAUAUCCAUUUAAUAAACACUAAAAUUGAGAAAAAUUAGUUUGGGGAUGAGGGCCUUCAUUCAUAAUAGCCAUAAUGCAUUAUCUAUGAUGUGAGCUUGAUUGAGCUUCUUUAAAAUGCAUAAAGAAUUUGAACAACAAAA